AGAAGCGCUGCCGCCACCGCAUCGCGCAGCUCUUUGCCGUCGGAGCGCUUGUUUGCUGCCUCGUACUCCUCCAUUUAUCCGCCAUGAUAAGUGCCAGCCGAGCUGCAGCAGCCCGUCUCGUGGGCGCCGCAGCCUCCCGGGGCCCUACGGCCGCCCGCCACCAGGAUAGCUGGAAUGGCCUUAGUCAUGAGGCUUUUAGACUUGUUUCAAGGCGGGAUUAUGCAUCAGAAGCAAUCAAGGGAGCAGUUGUUGGUAUUGAUUUGGGUACUACCAACUCCUGCGUGGCAGUUAUGGAAGGUAAACAAGCAAAGGUGCUGGAGAAUGCCGAAGGUGCCAGAACCACCCCUUCAGUUGUGGCCUUUACAGCAGAUGGUGAGCGACUUGUUGGAAUGCCGGCCAAGCGACAGGCUGUCACCAACCCAAACAAUACAUUUUAUGCUACCAAGCGUCUCAUUGGCCGGCGAUAUGAUGAUCCUGAAGUACAGAAAGACAUUAAAAAUGUUCCCUUUAAAAUUGUCCGUGCCUCCAAUGGUGAUGCCUGGGUUGAGGCUCAUGGGAAAUUGUAUUCUCCGAGUCAGAUUGGAGCAUUUGUGUUGAUGAAGAUGAAAGAGACUGCAGAAAAUUACUUGGGGCACACAGCAAAAAAUGCUGUGAUCACAGUCCCAGCUUAUUUCAAUGACUCGCAGAGACAGGCCACUAAAGAUGCUGGCCAGAUAUCUGGACUGAAUGUGCUUCGGGUGAUUAAUGAGCCCACAGCUGCUGCUCUUGCCUAUGGUCUAGACAAAUCAGAAGACAAAGUCAUUGCUGUAUAUGAUUUAGGUGGUGGAACUUUUGAUAUUUCUAUCCUGGAAAUUCAGAAAGGAGUAUUUGAGGUGAAAUCCACAAAUGGGGAUACCUUCUUAGGUGGGGAAGACUUUGACCAGGCCUUGCUACGGCACAUUGUGAAGGAGUUCAAGAGAGAGACAGGGGUUGAUUUGACUAAAGACAACAUGGCACUUCAGAGGGUACGGGAAGCUGCUGAAAAGGCUAAAUGUGAACUCUCCUCAUCUGUGCAGACUGACAUCAAUUUGCCCUAUCUUACAAUGGAUUCUUCUGGACCCAAGCAUUUGAAUAUGAAGUUGACCCGUGCUCAAUUUGAAGGGAUUGUCACUGAUCUAAUCAGAAGGACUAUCGCUCCAUGCCAAAAAGCUAUGCAAGAUGCAGAAGUCAGCAAGAGUGACAUAGGAGAAGUGAUUCUUGUGGGUGGCAUGACUAGGAUGCCCAAGGUUCAGCAGACUGUACAGGAUCUUUUUGGCAGAGCCCCAAGUAAAGCUGUCAAUCCUGAUGAGGCUGUGGCCAUUGGAGCUGCCAUUCAGGGAGGUGUGUUGGCCGGCGAUGUCACGGAUGUGCUGCUCCUUGAUGUCACUCCCCUGUCUCUGGGUAUUGAAACUCUAGGAGGUGUCUUUACCAAACUUAUUAAUAGGAAUACCACUAUUCCAACCAAGAAGAGCCAGGUAUUCUCUACUGCCGCUGAUGGUCAAACGCAAGUGGAAAUUAAAGUGUGUCAGGGUGAAAGAGAGAUGGCUGGAGACAACAAACUCCUUGGACAGUUUACUUUGAUUGGAAUUCCACCAGCCCCUCGUGGAGUUCCUCAGAUUGAAGUUACAUUUGACAUUGAUGCCAAUGGGAUAGUACAUGUUUCUGCUAAAGAUAAAGGCACAGGACGUGAGCAGCAGAUUGUAAUCCAGUCUUCUGGUGGAUUAAGCAAAGAUGAUAUUGAAAAUAUGGUUAAAAAUGCAGAGAAAUAUGCUGAAGAAGACCGGCGAAAGAAGGAACGAGUUGAAGCAGUUAAUAUGGCUGAAGGAAUCAUUCACGACACAGAAACCAAGAUGGAAGAAUUCAAGGACCAAUUACCUGCUGAUGAGUGCAACAAGCUGAAAGAAGAGAUUUCCAAAAUGAGGGAGCUCCUGGCUAGAAAAGACAGCGAAACAGGAGAAAAUAUUAGACAGGCAGCAUCCUCUCUUCAGCAGGCAUCACUGAAGCUGUUCGAAAUGGCAUACAAAAAGAUGGCAUCUGAGCGAGAAGGCUCUGGAAGUUCUGGCACUGGGGAACAAAAGGAAGAUCAAAAGGAGGAAAAACAGUAAUAAUAGCAGAAAUUUUGAAGCCAGAAGGACAACAUAUGAAGCUUAGGAGUGAAGAGACUUCCUGAGCAGAAAUGGGCGAACUUCAGUCUUUUUACUGUGUUUUUGCAGUAUUCUAUAUAUAAUUUCCUUAAUUUGUAAAUUUAGUGACCAUUAGCUAGUGAUCAUUUAAUGGACAGUGAUUCUAACAGUAUAAAGUUCACAAUAUUCUAUGUCCCUAGCCUGUCAUUUUUCAGCUGCAUGUAAAAGGAGGUAGGAUGAAUUGAUCAUUAUAAAGAUUUAACUAUUUUAUGCUGAAGUGACCAUAUUUUCAAGGGGUGAAACCAUCUCGCACACAGCAAUGAAGGUAGUCAUCCAUAGACUUGAAAUGAGACCACAUAUGGGGAUGAGAUCCUUCUAGUUAGCCUAGUACUGCUGUACUGGCCUGUAUGUACAUGGGGUCCUUCAACUGAGGCCUUGCAAGUCAAGCUGGCUGUGCCAUGUUUGUAGAUGGGGCAGAGGAAUCUAGAACAAUGGGAAACUUAGCUAUUUAUAUUAGGUACAGCUAUUAAAACAAGGUAGGAAUGAGGCUAGACCUUUAACUUCCCUAAGGCAUACUUUUCUAGCUACCUUCUGCCCUGUGUCUGGCACCUACAUCCUUGAUGAUUGUUCUCUUACCCAUUCUGGAAUUUUUUUUUUUUUAAAUAAAUACAGAAAGCAUCUUGAUCUCUUGUUUGUGAGGGGUGAUGCCCUGAGAUUUAGCUUCAAGAAUAUGCCAUGGCUCAUGCUUCCCAUAUUUCCCAAAGAGGGAAAUACAGGAUUUGCUAACACUGGUUAAAAAUGCAAAUUCAAGAUUUGGAAGGGCUGUUAUAAUGAAAUAAUGAGCAGUAUCAGCAUGUGCAAAUCUUGUUUGAAGGAUUUUAUUUUCUCCCCUUAGACCUUUGGUACAUUUAGAAUCUUGAAAGUUUCUAGAUCUCUAACAUGAAAGUUUCUAGAUCUCUAACAUGAAAGUUUUUAGAUCUCUAACAUGAAAACCAAGGUGGCUAUUUUCAGGUUGCUUUCAGCUCCAAGUAGAAAUAACCAGAAUUGGCUUACAUUAAAGAAACUGCAUCUAGAAAUAAGUCCUAAGAUACUAUUUCUAUGGCUCAAAAAUAAAAGGAACCCAGAUUUCUUUCCCUAUUUCUGCUUUUCUGUCCUCAGUGUACUGGCUUGUCCCAAAUUCUCUGAUGUAGUUCUAAUAAUUAUCAUGUGCUGACAACCUGAGCAGAAAGGCAACUACAUCUUUAUUCAAUGUUAAGAUUUCCCAAAAGUCUUCCAGCACAUUUCCCUUAUGUUUCAUGGAUGAAUGUCAUAUGCCAUGUUCAAAAGAGUCUGUUAUCAAGAUGGGCUUAGAAUAUCAGACACAAUGGCUCCUUUUAUAAUGUUUUGUAAUAUGUAGAAAUGAGAUUACUGUAUUUCCAAAAAUCAGUAUAAGAAAUCAAUUUAAUUUGCAAGUAUGAAGGAAGUGAUUUAGACAACAUUUUUGGAAGAUUCAGUGCUUGUUAACACCCAUGUAAAAGAUUCUUGGGAUUCGUGAAAAAUUCUAGGCUCAGGUUUCCAACCACAUGAACACUCAAUGGGAACAUUGUAGGAUUAUGAAGGAUUGUUAUAUGGUGUGUUGGAAAAUAACUUUUAGCAUUUUUGGUUGGCCCUUGCCCACUGCCUCUACUGUCUCCUAAAGAUAACUUUAAAAGCCCUCCAGGAUUUCCAAAGUACUCCAGUUGAGAACUACUGGCUUAAUGCUAGUCAAGAUUCAUCCUUGGGAUCAGAGAGAGGAGCCAAAUGCCCAAGCAAAAUAUAUAUUUGAGUUCUAUUAGGAGGGAGAAGUUGCUUGGGUAUGGGUGGACACAGUAUUUCAGUCACCUAUCAGUAAAGCUAAUAGCAUAAAUAGCAAGAAGGUAUAUGGAGAUUUCCUACAGCCAAUAGGAUAUAUAUCUAGAAUAAGAUUUACUGUAAGAAAGAAACUGGCUCACAAUUAUGGAACCGAGGUCCCACCCACAGUCCACUGCUGGGAAAGCUGUUGGGGUAAAAUUUCAGUGACCAGGAACACAGUGGUGUCCUAGUCCGAGGUUAGAAGAAUAUGGAUGUCUUAGCUCUGGCAGUUCUAUAUAGGCCCUUAACUGAUUAGAUGAUGUCCACUCACAUCAAAGCAGAGCAAUCUCCAAUUCAAUACUAAUCUCUUCUGGAGAGAGACAAAUGUUUAACCCGUUAAAUGGCAUCAAUGGCUAAACUGACACAUAAAAUUAACUAUCACAAAAGGCAAAAA